AGAGCCCGUCCCGGGCGCCGGCAAGCGAGCUCCGGCCGCGGCGGCAGCGCCAUCCCGGGCCGCGGGCAGCCGCCCCUCGCCCUCCGCGUCCGGAACUGCCUUCGCCUUCCCGCGACCCCGCAGCAGCCGGCCCUCGGGGCGCCACGAACGCUGUCCCCUCUGUGGAGCAGAGACCCCCUUCCCCUUCUUAGGGGGUGUCGCCUCGGGGAUCGCUGAGCGCUAGGGGUCCAGGAGGCGGGGACGGGAGCGCCGUGACCCGCCAUGGCUCAAGCGGCCAAACAGCUGAAGAAAAUCAAAGACAUCGAGGCGCAGGCCCUCCAGGAGCAGAAGGAGAAGGAGGAAUCCAACAGGAAGCGGAGAAACCGCUCCCGUGACCGAAAGAAGAAGGCCGAUGCUGCUACCAGCUUUCUGAGAGCAGCAAGAUCAGGUAACUUGGACAAAGCUUUGGAUCACCUGCGGAAUGGGGUAGAUAUUAACACCUGUAACCAGAAUGGGUUGAAUGGCUUGCAUCUGGCUUCUAAGGAAGGCCAUGUGAAAAUGGUGGUUGAACUUCUGCACAAAGAAAUCAUUCUAGAAACGACAACCAAGAAGGGGAACACGGCCCUGCACAUCGCUGCUCUAGCCGGGCAGGAUGAGGUGGUCCGGGAGCUUGUCAACUAUGGAGCCAACGUCAACGCCCAGUCACAGAAAGGUUUUACACCCCUGUACAUGGCAGCACAAGAGAACCACUUGGAAGUGGUUAAGUUUUUACUGGAAAAUGGAGCUAACCAGAAUGUAGCCACAGAAGACGGCUUCACGCCUCUGGCGGUAGCCCUGCAGCAGGGCCAUGAGAACGUCGUCGCGCACCUCAUCAACUACGGCACCAAGGGGAAGGUGCGCCUCCCGGCCCUGCACAUCGCGGCCCGCAACGACGACACGCGCACGGCUGCGGUGCUGCUGCAGAACGACCCCAACCCGGACGUGCUUUCCAAGACGGGAUUCACGCCCCUGCACAUUGCGGCUCACUACGAGAACCUCAACGUGGCCCAGUUGCUCCUCAACAGAGGAGCCAGCGUCAAUUUCACACCACAGAACGGCAUCACGCCACUGCACAUCGCCUCCCGCAGGGGCAACGUGAUCAUGGUGCGGCUGCUGCUGGAUCGGGGAGCCCAGAUAGAAACCAAGACCAAGGACGAAUUGACACCUCUCCACUGUGCAGCUCGAAAUGGGCACGUGCGAAUCUCAGAGAUCCUGCUGGACCACGGGGCACCAAUCCAAGCCAAAACCAAGAACGGCCUGUCCCCAAUUCACAUGGCGGCUCAGGGAGACCACCUCGACUGUGUCCGGCUCCUGUUGCAAUACGACGCAGAGAUAGACGACAUCACCCUGGACCACCUGACCCCACUCCACGUGGCUGCCCACUGUGGACACCACAGGGUGGCUAAGGUCCUUCUGGAUAAAGGGGCCAAACCCAACUCCAGAGCCCUGAAUGGCUUUACCCCCUUACACAUCGCCUGCAAAAAGAACCACGUCCGUGUCAUGGAGCUGCUGCUGAAGACGGGAGCCUCGAUCGACGCGGUCACCGAGUCUGGCCUGACACCUCUCCACGUGGCCUCCUUCAUGGGGCACCUUCCCAUCGUGAAGAACCUCCUGCAGCGGGGGGCGUCGCCCAACGUCUCCAACGUGAAAGUGGAGACCCCGCUACACAUGGCAGCCAGAGCCGGGCACACGGAAGUGGCCAAAUAUUUACUCCAGAACAAAGCCAAAGUCAAUGCCAAGGCCAAGGAUGACCAGACCCCACUUCACUGUGCAGCUCGCAUCGGCCACACAAACAUGGUGAAGCUCCUGCUGGAAAAUAACGCCAACCCCAACCUGGCCACCACCGCCGGGCACACCCCCCUGCACAUUGCAGCCCGUGAGGGCCAUGUGGAAACAGUCCUGGCCCUUCUGGAAAAGGAAGCAUCCCAGGCCUGCAUGACCAAGAAAGGAUUUACCCCUCUGCACGUGGCGGCCAAGUACGGGAAGGUGCGGGUGGCAGAGCUGCUGCUGGAGCGGGACGCACACCCGAAUGCUGCCGGAAAAAAUGGCCUGACCCCCCUGCACGUGGCCGUCCAUCACAACAACCUGGACAUCGUCAAGCUGCUGCUUCCCCGGGGCGGCUCCCCGCACAGCCCUGCCUGGAAUGGCUACACCCCUUUGCACAUCGCUGCCAAGCAGAACCAGGUGGAGGUGGCCCGUAGUCUGCUGCAGUAUGGGGGCUCAGCAAACGCCGAGUCGGUGCAAGGUGUGACGCCCCUUCACCUGGCCGCCCAGGAGGGCCACGCAGAGAUGGUGGCUCUGCUGCUCUCGAAACAAGCCAAUGGCAACCUGGGGAACAAGAGCGGACUCACUCCCCUCCAUCUGGUAGCACAAGAAGGCCACGUUCCAGUGGCAGAUGUGCUGAUCAAACACGGCGUCAUGGUGGACGCCACCACCCGGAUGGGCUACACUCCCCUCCAUGUGGCCAGUCACUAUGGAAACAUCAAGCUGGUGAAGUUUCUGCUGCAGCACCAGGCAGAUGUCAAUGCCAAGACCAAGCUAGGAUACAGCCCCCUGCACCAGGCAGCCCAGCAGGGACACACAGACAUCGUGACUCUGCUUCUGAAAAACGGUGCUUCCCCAAACGAGGUCAGCUCGGAUGGAACCACACCUCUGGCCAUAGCCAAGCGCUUGGGCUACAUUUCUGUCACCGACGUGCUCAAGGUCGUCACGGAUGAAACCAGUUUCGUGUUAGUCAGUGAUAAGCAUCGAAUGAGUUUCCCUGAGACAGUUGAUGAGAUCCUGGAUGUCUCGGAAGAUGAAGGAACUGCUCAUAUAACUAUAAUGGGGGAAGAACUCAUCAGCUUCAAGGCUGAGAGGCGGGAUUCCAGGGAUGUUGAUGAAGAGAAGGAGCUGCUGGAUUUUGUGCCGAAGCUAGACCAAGUGGUGGAAUCUCCAGCCAUCCCCAGGAUUCCCUGUGCCAUGCCUGAGACAGUGGUGAUCAGGUCAGAAGAGCAGGAGCAGGCAUCUAAAGAGUAUGAUGAGGACUCCCUCAUCCCCAGCAGCCCGGCCACCGAGACCUCAGACAACAUCAGCCCGGUGGCCAGCCCGGUGCAUACAGGGUUUCUGGUGAGCUUCAUGGUUGACGCCCGGGGUGGUUCCAUGAGAGGAAGUCGCCACAACGGCCUGCGAGUGGUGAUCCCGCCACGGACGUGCGCAGCGCCCACCCGCAUCACCUGCCGCCUGGUCAAGCCCCAGAAGCUCAGCACGCCGCCCCCACUGGCCGAGGAGGAGGGCCUGGCCAGCAGGAUCAUAGCACUGGGGCCCACGGGGGCACAGUUCCUGAGCCCUGUAAUCGUGGAGAUCCCGCACUUUGCCUCCCAUGGCCGUGGAGACCGCGAGCUCGUGGUUCUGAGGAGCGAAAACGGCUCCGUGUGGAAGGAGCACAGGAGCCGCUAUGGAGAGAGCUACCUGGAUCAGAUCCUCAACGGGAUGGACGAAGAGCUGGGGAGCCUGGAGGAGCUAGAGAAGAAGAGGGUGUGCCGAAUCAUCACCACCGACUUCCCGCUGUACUUCGUGAUCAUGUCACGGCUCUGCCAGGACUACGACACCAUCGGUCCCGAAGGGGGCUCCCUGAAGAGCAAGCUGGUGCCCCUGGUACAGGCAACGUUCCCGGAGAAUGCCGUCACCAAGAGAGUGAAGCUGGCUCUGCAGGCCCAGCCUGUCCCGGAUGAGCUUGUCACUAAGCUCCUGGGCAACCAGGCCACAUUCAGCCCCAUUGUCACCGUGGAGCCCCGGCGCCGGAAGUUCCACCGCCCCAUUGGGCUUCGGAUCCCACUACCUCCUUCCUGGACCGACAACCCGAGGGACAGCGGGGAGGGAGACACCACCAGCCUGCGCCUGCUUUGCAGCGUCAUUGGAGGAACAGACCAAGCCCAGUGGGAAGACAUAACAGGAACCACCAAACUUGUAUAUGCCAACGAGUGCGCCAACUUCACCACCAAUGUCUCUGCCAGGUUUUGGCUGUCGGACUGUCCUCGGACUGCUGAGGCUGUGAACUUUGCCACCCUGCUGUACAAAGAGCUCACUGCAGUGCCCUACAUGGCCAAAUUCGUCAUCUUUGCCAAGAUGAAUGACCCCCGAGAGGGGCGCCUGCGCUGCUACUGCAUGACAGAUGAUAAAGUGGACAAGACCCUGGAGCAGCAUGAGAACUUCGUGGAGGUGGCCCGGAGCAGGGACAUAGAGGUGUUGGAAGGAAUGUCCCUGUUUGCAGAACUCUCUGGGAACCUGGUGCCUGUGAAGAAAGCUGCCCAGCAGCGGAGCUUCCACUUCCAGUCAUUUCGGGAGAACCGUCUGGCCAUGCCUGUAAAGGUGAGGGACAGCAGUCGAGAGCCGGGAGGGUCCCUGUCGUUUCUGCGCAAGGCGAUGAAGUACGAGGACACCCAGCACAUUCUCUGCCACCUGAACAUCACCAUGCCCCCCUGCGCCAAGGGAAGUGGAGCCGAAGAUAGGAGAAGGACCCCGACGCCCCUGGCCCUGCGAUACAGCAUUCUCAGUGAGUCCACACCAGGUUCUCUCAGUGGGACAGAGCAGGCAGAGAUGAAGAUGGCUGUUAUCUCAGAGCACCUCGGUCUCAGCUGGGCAGAGUUGGCCCGGGAGCUGCAGUUCAGUGUGGAAGACAUCAACAGGAUCCGAGUGGAAAAUCCCAACUCCCUGUUGGAGCAGAGUGUGGCCUUGCUGAACCUCUGGGUCAUCCGUGAAGGCCAAAACGCAAACAUGGAGAAUCUGUACACAGCCCUGCAGAGCAUUGACCGUGGCGAGAUCGUGAACAUGCUGGAGGGUUCCGGCCGACAGAGCCGCAACUUGAAGCCAGACAGGCGGCACACCGACCGCGACUACUCGCUGUCACCCUCCCAGAUGAAUGGUUACUCCUCACUGCAGGACGAGCUGCUGUCCCCUGCCUCCCUGGGCUGUGCACUUUCCUCUCCGCUACGUGCAGACCAGUACUGGAAUGAGGUGGCCGUCCUAGACGCCAUCCCCUUGGCGGCCACGGAGCAUGACACCAUGCUGGAGAUGUCUGACAUGCAGGUGUGGUCUGCGGGCCUCACGCCUUCUCUGGUCACUGCUGAGGACUCCUCUCUGGAGUGUAGCAAGGCUGAGGACUCUGAUGCCACAGGUCACGAGUGGAAGUUGGAGGGGGCACUCUCAGAGGAACCGCGGGGCCCCGAGUUGGGCUCUCUGGAACUUGUGGAGGACGACACAGUGGAUUCAGAUGCCACAAAUGGCCUUAUCGAUUUGCUUGAACAGGAGGAAGGUCAGAGGUCAGAAGAGAAGCUGCCAGGUUCUAAGAGGCAGGAUGACGCGACAGGUGCAGGGCAGGACUCAGAGAAUGAAGUGUCUCUUGUUUCAGGCCAUCAGAGGGGGCAAGCCCGAAUCACACAUUCCCCCACCGUGAGUCAGGUGACGGAGAGGAGUCAGGACAGACUGCAGGACUGGGAUGCAGACGGCUCGAUUGUCUCAUACCUGCAAGAUGCUGCACAAGGUUCCUGGCAAGAGGAGGUCACGCAAGGUCCACACUCAUUCCAGGGAACAAGUACCAUGACUGAAGGGCUAGAGCCCGGUGGAUCUCAGGAGUACGAGAAGGUCCUGGUGUCUGUAAGUGAGCACACGUGGACAGAACAGCCCGAGGCUGAGAGCUCCCAGGCCGACAGGGACCGGAGGCAGCAAGGCCAAGAAGAGCAGGUGCAGGAGGCCAAGAACACCUUCACCCAAGUGGUGCAGGGGAAUGAGUUUCAGAAUAUUCCAGGGGAGCAGGUGACAGAGGAGCAAUUCACGGAUGAGCAGGGCAACAUUGUCACCAAGAAGAUCAUUCGCAAGGUGGUUCGACAGAUAGACUUGUCCAGCGCCGAUGCCGCCCAGGAGCACGAGGAGGAUCACACCUCGACACCCAACCCCUGAACCCCACACACUCUGCCAUGCACACAGGAGGAGAGCUGGACCUGAGGGCCACCGCAGCGGUGCACACAUUCCUCUGGGCUGACGGCAUGACCUCUGUAAGGGACUCCUGCUAGUCCCCUCUUGGCAUGAAUGACUGACUGUAGACGCAUGACCUCCAGGCUUCAAUCCUGCCUCUUGCAAUGACAGCUGAUCUGUCGGAACCAGGACACAAAAGCAGCAAGAAGCGGGGAGAGAGAGGGAUAGAAAACAAGCGCAGGAGAGCCUGCGAACGCAAAAGUGAAUGAGGGCUUUUUGUGGCUGGGGAUGGGUUUUGGUUUUGGGGUUUUUUUUUUAAAUUGUUUUGACUUCGUACAGGGUACUUUUUCCCAACCUCAUCUGUCAGAAAUCCAUGUGGGCUUCCUGGAAAGAAAAAAAAAAAAAAGAAAACUAGGCAUGAAAUCAGUUUAACACCUUAAUCUUAAGCCAUGUCCUCAUCUGCCCACCCUCCCCAACCCACAUACCUCCAUUCCACUUGUGACACCCCCUCGACUCCCUGGUGACGCUCCUCCCAGAUCGCUCUACAUGACAUUCAGGACACACACACACACACACACACACCACUCGCCUCCACUGAAUCUACACACAGAUUUUACUGUGACUUCUGAAGCUGUAUAGACUCUGCUGUGGAUAAAUUGGAAUUUUUUAUGUUGUCUCUCUCUCUGCCAAUUUCAAUACGAAUCAUCUUCCAAUGGAAAAUCAUUACCUUGAAGAGUGCAUUCGGGGUUCCUUGUGUUAGGGACUUAAGAAUCUGAGGCGAGGACCCCCAGGCUUACCUGUAGGACUCAAAGGGAGCCAGGACCCCAUCUGAAAGGGUCUCCUCUCUCAGUUGGGGGACAGGCCGGUGGCUGACCCAGGAUUGCACCAGCAUGUCCAUAGAGAAGAGGUUUUCUAUGUCUUCAAGCACUAUAUCAUAGUCCGUGUUCAAAGUGUAAACUGUACAGUAAUCAGCCUUGUGUAUAUGAAAAACAAUAAAUACUAUGCAAACCAAUAGAAACAUUUAGCAGUACGUACAGAGCCUGACAGCGCAGCUCCUGAGGACUUCUGCGGCUGCAGGAGAAGGAGCUGUGGCCUGUCUUUCAGUGAAAGAGGAAGGAAAGGAGUAGGGCUAGUGAAUGUAUCUGCCAGGUCUUAGAAGUCAGGACCACCCAGGGUCUCCCAGAGUGAACUUGGUGCUCUAAGUCCAGGCAGCCUGCAGGCUGGGGACCCUGGGUGCAGGUGCCAGGCUCGAGGCUGUUCCCUGUCCUGCCUCAGUGCCUCCCCUCUGCCCAGCCCCUGUGGCCUCUUGGAGAGGCGAGCCAGGGGGCUCCCCGGACCGCAUGGCCGGUGAGAGUAGAGUCGGAGGCGGAGAGCCUGGACGCCCAGAGGCCGGGGCCAGGCUCUGGGUCAAGGCAGGAAGGAGACAGACAGCUGGCAGUUCCUCGCCUCGGUGCCAUCAGGGAGGAGCCUUAAGUUCCACUAGAGCCUCCGGCCCAGGGAGGCCAGAAUCAGCACAAUCCCGGCCCCGCCCUCGCGGCGGGCGCCCCCAGGGCCAGGAGAGAGAGACAGGGCUGGCUCCUCUCGCCCCUGGAGCCGCGGUGUGGACGGCCCGGCCCCGUCCGCCCCGCCGCUCUGCGGGAGUGUCCUCGGGACACACUUAAACCUUCCAAGUAGCACAGAAGCCCCCUCCACGUCAGAGGCCCCCUGGCCGCGGGGCCUGUGAGCGGAGAGGGGCCCUGCUUCCCACACAAAUCCGCCCCGGUGCACCCCCGGCCAGGCAGGCCCCGGGGCGGCCUAGGCGCCUUGUCGGCCGGGGGUGGGGCUGCUUUUGCUUCCUUUAGAGGGGCGGGCAGGGAGAGGAAGCUCUAGCUCCGGGCCUGAGUUUCCCCGAGGCUGCGUCGGAGGAGCUGCAGGGCGAGCCCGGACGGCUGCCGUCUCCGCCAGAGGCCACCCCGGCCCGGCCUCCAGGGCGCAGAGGCGCCCCCCUCCAUCCUCCCCCAUCCCGGGGGCCACGGCAGGGGGGCCGCACAGCGCGGCUGGGACCGAUUCGGUGACGGCCCAAGGAAGCUGGGCUCAGGGCUCGCCUCUCCCGCCUCGAUCCUGCACCUUCCUCUCCCAGGUCGCUGCUGCAGCCAACCCAGUAGCCCCCUUAGCGCCCCCGCGGACCCCGCAGCUCCAGACUCCGCUUUGGCACCUCUGCUCCGGCUGGCAUGGCUGCACGCUCCGGCUGCUAGUAGGAGCCGUUAGGGGAGGAGUUUGGGGUCUCCACACGAUGCCUAGAGAAUGCUGCAGUCUGCACAUUAGACGCUUUUUAGAAGUUUUGAAAUUACCUUGAUUUUUUUAAUUGUUAUGAAAAUGGAUCUUUUCUUGACUCUCCCACAUGCUCUGUUAUGGGAGAGAAUCCCCUACCCUACUCUGAUGUAUAGACCAUUCUCCCUUCACCAGCCGAACCAAUGUCAAAAUUAAUAAAGAAAUGGACUAAUGGCA